ACUCCAACGCUGGGUGACAUUGAGCUCACCAGCGCCACCGUCCCCGGCGAAGUUCUGCGCUGGUCGGCGGAGUAGCAAGUGGCCAUGGGGAGCCUCAGCGGUCUGCGCCUGGCAGCAGGAAGCUGUUUUAGGUUAUGUGAAAGAGAUGUUUCCUCAUCUCUAAGGCUUACCAGAAGCUCUGAUUUGAAGAGAAUAAAUGGAUUUUGCACAAAACCACAGGAAAGUCCCGGAGCUCCAUCCCGCACUUACAACAGAGUGCCUUUACACAAACCUACGGAUUGGCAGAAAAAGAUCCUCAUAUGGUCAGGUCGCUUCAAAAAGGAAGAUGAAAUCCCAGAGACUGUCUCGUUGGAGAUGCUUGAUGCUGCAAAGAACAAGAUGCGAGUGAAGAUCAGCUAUCUAAUGAUUGCCCUGACGGUGGUAGGAUGCAUCUUCAUGGUUAUUGAGGGCAAGAAGGCUGCCCAAAGACACGAGACUUUAACAAGCUUGAACUUAGAAAAGAAAGCUCGUCUGAAAGAGGAAGCAGCUAUGAAGGCCAAAACAGAGUAGCAGAGGUAUCCGUGUUGGCUGGAUUUUGAAAAUCCAGGAAUUAUGUUAUAACGUGCCUGUAUUAAAAAGGAUGUGGUAUGAGGAUCCAUUUCAUAAAGUAUGAUUUGCCCAAACCUGUACCAUUUCCGUAUUUCUGCUGUAGAAGUAGAAAUAAAUUUUCUUAAAUAAUGACUGUGUUUUAUUGUUUUGAUCCAAGUCAAGUGUAGCCUCUCAGCCUUUUGGAGAAAAAUGAAACAAUUUAUUUCAACUUGAAUACCAACUCUUCAGAGAAGCAGGUACCAUAUCUUACUUCUCUUCCCAUUAUCAAAGUAACCUCUCCACAGGCGAACUCAUUUUGAGGAGAUAAGGAAGGCCAGUUGAGUAUAUGGCCCAGGUGCAGCUUGGAGGGCCAGCCUUCUCAAAUGUCCUGGUGUACUGGUGGGGAGGCUGCCCCCUAAUAGAGCGAGCGCUGAGAAGCAGCCAGACCACAUUCUAUAAUCUUUGAACAUGCUGGCAGAUGGAGGCUUUUAGGAGAAUAGUUUUUUAAACAUUCUGACAAGGUCCAGCCAGGAAUUUCUAAGGACUUAGAAAUCCCAGCGUCAUGGAGUUGCUUGGGGUCAACACAAGUCACCUCUUAGCUUCAUGCCUUAGAAUUCUCAACUGGCUGUUUUCUUACCACCUGAGAAACUAAAUUUCUCAAUUAUAAAAAUCUCAUGUAUUAUUACUGUUAGAAGUAUUUGCACCUCAUAUAUAUCUCAUUUACAGUUUGACCUUGGGAUAUCGAGUUGUCUCAUAUUUAGGUAUGAAUACAGGUUUCUAUUUUAAACAUUGAUUCUCACAUGCUUCUUAAUUAUUCAUGGAUGACAAGCCAUUAUAGUAGUCCCUUCUUAUCCACGGCUUUGUUUUCUGUGGUUUCAGUUACCUGAGGUCUGAAAAUAUUAAAUGGAAAAUUCCUAUAACAAUGCAUAAGUUAUAGAUUACAUACCAUUCAGUGUAGCAUGAUGAAAUCUCUUGCCAAUCUGUUCCAUCCACCUGGGAUGUGAAUCAUCCCUCUCUCUGGUGUAUUCACACUGUAUGUGCUAGCCGUCUCUGUUACGAGAUCAGCUGUCGUGGAAUCAGUGCUAGUGUUCAGGUAACUCUUAUUUAAUAAUUGCCUCAAAGUGCAUUGUGCUGUGCCUAAUUUAUAAAAUAAACGGUAUCAUAGGUAUGUAUGUAUACGAAAAACAUAGUAUAUGCAGGGUUGGGUACUAUCCACAGUUUCAGGCAUCUACUGGGGGGUCUUGGAAUAUAUCCCCAGAGGGUAAGGGGUGACUACUGUAUACAGCCAUGCCAACAUGCUGGUUCUCAGAGAGUUAUAAGAGAGAUUAAAAAUACAUGCAGCUGUUUGGGCACUUUCUUCCCAAAUAAAAUACCCAGUAAAAUGUAACAUACUACCUAUAGCUUGAUAAUCUAUCUGAGGAUGUUUAUGAUGUCUGUCUAUAUACUUUAAUUUGGCCUUAGCUUCUUUGUAGGUAUCAAGUUAUCACUUGCAAAUUUAUUUUCAAAAAGCAUAGUUUCUUGUACAUUUUAGAAGAUUAGUUUUUCUUAUUUUGGGACACCUACACCAAUGUUUUAAAUGUGGAUAAAUUUUAAUGUGGAAUUUCUUUUAAAAAUAAUCCUCUUCAUAGAGCAAUACAACAAAAAUGUGUUGUAUCUUGGAGAUUUACAUUAUAAAUGUAGUAACAUUUAUGAGCUUAAAUUUAAUGAAACCUUUUUUUUUUUUUUGAGACAGUCUUGCACUGUCGCCCAGGCUAGAGUGCAGGGCAUGAUCUCAGCUCACUGCAACCUCCGUCUCCCGGGUUCAAGCAAUUCUCGUGCCUCAGCCUCCUCAGUAACUGGCAUUAUAGGUGUGCACCACCACACCUGGCUAAUUUUUGUAUUUUUCAUAAAGACGGGGGUUUCACCAUGUUGGCCAGGCUGGUCUCAAACUCCUGACCUCAGGUGAUCAGCCUCCCUCGGCCUCCCAAAGUGCUGGGAUUACAGGCAUGAGCCAUGGUGCCUGGCCAAACGUUUUUAUUACAAAUAUUACAUUAAACUAAAGCUCACAACUGUUAUUAUGCAUCAGGAAUUAACAGUCAUUUCUCAUUUGUGUUAUUCUCCUAUUUGAUAACAUAUAGUGACUAUCUCUUUAUGGGUUAAAUAUCAGUUUCUUGGCCAGAAUUCAAGAUCUGCCCCUAACUAAUCCUACUUCUCCCAGUACCCUUACAGCACUCCUACCCUACUAGUAACUCUGAUAUCUCAUAGUCCUCAGAUUUAUCAAGCAAACGAAACUGAAUGAGCACUACUAUAAGGUACCACAAACUACAAAAGGAGACAGUUUUGCCCUUGUUGCUUUCAGUUAAAUUAUUGUGCUAUUUUUUGCUUAAUUUCUAGGUUUUUUUUGCGUGUUUAUCAUGUCUCCGUAGGUAAAGUGGGCAGAAAUCUUUUUCUACUUUACAUUUCCUGUAAGUGCUGUUUGUUUGAAUAAAGUUAAUGUGUGAGGUUA